AAACGCCCAGGUUCACCCAACGCCAGAGGCUCGUCCUCAAUUCCCGCGAGGCCCCCGGAGGUGCUGGGGUCCCUGCAGGGCCGGGCCACCUGCCGUGGAGCUCAGGCCGCGCCAGAAUCGGAUCCGGGAAGCUGCGCGCCAUGAGCAGCUCCCUGCGGCCGGGCCCCAGCCGCUGGCGGCGGGCGGCCAGCAUCGUCCUGGCGGCUGGCUGGUCGCGCCCGGAGACCGCCACCCCGCCGUCGCGCCCGCCGCCGGCCGAGGGCUUCCGGCUGCUGCUGCUGCAGCGCUCCCCGCACCAAGGCUUCAUGCCGGGCGCGCACGUCUUCUCCGGCGGAGUGCUGGAUGCGGCCGACCGCUCGGCGGACUGGCUGGGCCUCUUCGCGCCGCACCACGGGCCGCCGCGCUUCGGCCUGGGCCCGGCGCCAUUCAGCCGCACCGCUUUCCCGUCGCUGCCCGACACCGAUGACCACAAGACCGACAACACUGGGACGCUGCCUGAGGACGUAGCCUUCCGCAUCUGCGCCGUGCGGGAGGCCUUUGAGGAGGCGGGCGUGCUGCUGCUGCGGCCCAGGACUUCCCCACCAGGCCCAGCACCCGGGCCUGGCCUCGCCCUGGAGCCACCGCCGGGCCUGGCCUCCUGGCGCGACCGCGUGCGCCAGGACCCGCGCCACUUCCUGCGGCUGUGCGCCCACCUCGACUGCACACCCGACAUCUGGGCGCUGCACAACUGGAGCGCCUGGCUCACCCCUUUCUUGCGGGGCACCACUCGCCGCUUUGACACGGCCUUCUUCCUGUGCUGCCUGCGCGAGCCGCCGCCCGUCUACCCCGACUUGGCGGAGGUGGUGGGCUACCAGUGGUCAUCUCCAUCAGAGGCAACUGAAAGUUUCUUAUCAAAAGAAAUUUGGUUGCCACCCCCACAGUUCUACGAAGUGAGAAGACUUGCAAACUUUGCCUCUCUCUCUGACUUGCACAAAUUUUGUUUGGGUCGUGCAUUAGAAGGACUGGAAAGGUGGCUGCCGAUCAUCUUGUUAACUGCUGAUGGGAUGGUCCAUCUUUUACCAGGUGAUGAGCUAUAUUUAGAAGAUUCAGACUUUUUGGAAAAUCUUAUGUCUACUGAAAAAAAGACUGAGGAAAUCAUGAAGGAAGGCAAGCAGUUUCACCGGAUAGUGACAUACCAUCGCCACCUUUAUGAUAUCCACGUGACUGUUCAGCCAAAGUAUAAACACGUUUAUCCUAAGAACUCUGUAGUAAGAAAAAGCCAUUUGUAGGGUGCUUAAGCUUGUUUGUAAAAUGGCCUACUUGAAGUCCUCAUGAAUAAUGAGGGUUGACUUUCAUUUGCUUGAAACUUAAGGAAGUUUGUGCCUAUAAAAGUUACUGCAAUUCAGUAUUUCUUUAUUUUUUUCGAGACAGAGUCUCAAUCUGUCGCCCAGGCUGGAGUGCAGUGGCAUGAUAUAGGCUCACUGGAAGCUCUGCCUCAGGGGUUCAUGCCAUUCUCCUGCCUCAGCCUCCCGAGUAGCUGGGACUACAGGCGCCCGCCACCAUGCCCAGCUAAUUUUUUUUUGUAUUUUUAGUAGAGACGGGUUUUCACCGUGUUAGCCAGGAUGGUCUCAAUCUCUUGACCUCGUGAUACGCCCGCCUUGGCCUCCCAAAGUGCUGGGAUUACAGGUGUGGGCCACCACACCCAGCCUUUUUUUUUUUUUUUUUUUUUUUUUUUGAGACAGAGUGUCUCACUCUUGCCCAGAACCCAGGCUGGAGUGCAGUGGCCCAAUCUCGGCUCACUGCAACCUCCACCUCCCAGGUUCCAGCGAUUCUCAUGCCUCAGCCUCCUGAGUAGCUGGGACUAUAGGCAUGCACCACCAUGCCCCACUAAAUUUUGUAUUUUUAGUAGAAACAGAGUUUCACCAUGUUGGCCAGGCUGGUCUCGAUCUCCUGACCUCAUGAUCUGCCCGCCUUGGCCUCCCAAAGUGUGGGAUUACAGGCGUGAGCCACUGUGCCCAGCAUGGUGUUUCUUAUAUCAGGUGUUUUAGGGAGCUCGCUUGCUUAUUCCAUUCUUUAAUCCUUACAGUGUGCCACACGUAUAAAGUUUAUAACGUAUUAAUGAUCUCAUUACCCAAAACCAGAACAUAAUUUCACAAGGGUUCCUACUUCUGUAUUGUUUUAUUAUCUCAAAAAUUUAAAUAACAUGUUCUGCUGUUUAUUGUUCUUGUUAUCCACUGUAUUAGCACCUUCCCUGAUGUGCUUUGGAGGUUGAUCAAUGAAUUUCUGAGACUUUCUGCUGGAAUUACUUUAAGGGUGUCUUAUUAGAUGAUGAAAAGUUGGCUGAGACACCCUUCAAGUGACCAUGUCAUUGUUUUCUUGCUAUGUCUUUAGCUUAAUGAUUAAGAUACAAUUCUUUUUAAAAUCAAAUGGUAUUAGUUAUUAUGUUUCCCAAAUUAGAAAUCGAUUUUAGUUAACAUUUUAUUUUAUUUUAUUCUAUUUUAUUUAUUUUUGAGACAGAGUCUCGCUCUGUUGCCCAGGCUGGAGUACAAUGGCGCAAUCUCAGCUCACUCCAAUCUCCGCCUCCCAGGUUCAAGCGAUUUUUCUGCCUCAGCCUCCCGAGUAGCUGGGAUUACAGGCACCCACUACCAUGCCCAGCUAAUCUUUGUAUUUUUAGUAGAGACGGGGUUUCACCAUGUUGGCCAGUCCGGUCUCGAACUUCUGACCUGAGGUGAUCUGCCCACCUUGGCCUCACAAAGUGCUGAGAUUACAGGCUUGAGCCACCACGCCUGGCCUAGUUAGCAUUUUAAAGAAACACAAAGCCAUAACAAAAACCAUCAUUGUUUGUAUUCCACACUGUUAAUGAAUGUAAAGAGGUUAGAAAUGUAGUGUUUGAUUAAUGAUGUUUAUUUUUACUGUAUUUAAUAUGAGUAAUUUUUCAUCAUCUUUCAAGAGGAAUAAUGUUUAUUGAUUAAAGGUGAGAAAUGAUAGUUAAGACACCAAUUCCAUGUCCAGAUCUUUGACUGUAUCAUGCAUUGUACAAUUGAUUUCAUAUUUUAUGAAAUGCCUUAAUUUUCCUACUAUAACAUAAAGACAAUGAUGAAUAAAGUUUAUGUGUAUGAUUAAA